GAGGGCCGGCCCCCUGAAGCGCAAGAGAAGGAGGGGCGCGCAGGGAUCGCGCCUAGUCUCUCCGCCUGCGGAGCCGUGGGGUCCCGGCAGCCCGCAGGAGUGCUAAGUAAGGGUCCUUCAGGGCGGGAACCAGGUUCCAGGCAGGGACGCAGGCUACGUUCGAAUAAAAGUACCGAAGGUCAUAAGGCCCCAGUUCAGAUGGGACUUCCCCGCGUGACAGCACAGAGAUAACGGCCAGCCCUGGGCGAAGGUAGGAGAGCGGGCGUGCCAGGUUGGAGGGGUCAUUUCGUGGAGCGAGUUUAGGGGGAGCCCCCAGAAGCCCAGAGCAGUCAGGUCACACGACGGGCAGGAAGGAGUACCAGCAAAUACUUUUUAUUGAGCAUACAGGUAUUACGCUGGGUCUUUACAUAUCUCCUCCAAAUAAGUGAGUCCAAAUGGCAGGUAACUCGAAAGGUGAGAAAUUCAAGUCAGCUUUGAAAGACACAUUGCAUUUAAAGGAAAAACGGUAUUCGCAGAUGAUAAUACAGGAUGGAGUGGAUCAGAAAACACACUGAGGCUACUGAUCAUUCCCAUUUGCCAACUCACUGCAGUUGGCAAGAAAACUCUGUGACUCCAUGAGAUGGGAAAUUACACCAGCAGUCAAGGUAGCAAGGUUACCACCAAAGAAUAUGAUUUUGGUCUAGGGGCUCCAGUUUCUGAAGCUGAAAACUACCAGAAUACUCUCCAGCUAGAACAAGAAGUGAGAAACCAAGAUAGAUUCAUCUCGACACUGAAAUUACAGAUUGAAGAUCUCAAACAGACAAAUCAUGGCUUGGAAGAAUAUGUUAGGAAACUCUUGGAUAGUAAGGAGGUGGUAAGCAGUCAAGUAGAUGAUUUAACCAGCCACAAUGAGCAUCUUUGUAAAGAAUUGAUUAAAAUUGACCAACUAGCAGAGCAACUCGAAAAAGAGAAAAAUUUUGUGGUGGAUUCCGCCAACAAGGAACUUGAAGAAGCCAAGAUUGAUCUCAUUUGCCAGCAAAAUAAUAUUAUAGUAUUGGAAGAUACAAUAAAAAGGCUUAAAUCUAUAAUUUUAGAUACUGAAAAAGCACAAAAUAAAUCUCCUUCUAGACUUGAUUCCUUUGUCAAGACUUUGGAAGCAGACAAAGAUCACUAUAAGAGUGAAGCUCAACAUUUGAGAAAGAUGAUGCGAAGUAGGUCUAAAAGUCCAAGACGCCCAUCACCAACUGCCCGGGGUGCAAACUGUGAUGUAGAACUUUUGAAGACAACAACAAGAGAUCGUGAAGAACUUAAAUGCAUGCUGGAAAAAUAUGAGCGCCAUUUGGCAGAAAUUCAGGGUAAUGUCAAGGUUCUUAAAUCUGAGAGAGACAAGAUCUUCCUUCUUUAUGAACAGGCACAGGAAGAAAUUACCCGACUUCGACGAGAAAUGAUGAAAAGCUGUAAGAGUCCUAAAUCAACAACGGCACAUGCUAUUCUCCGGCGAGUGGAGACUGAAAGAGAUGUAGCCUUUACUGAUUUACGAAGAAUGACCACAGAACGAGAUAGUCUAAGGGAGAGGCUAAAGAUUGCUCAAGAGACAGCAUUUAAUGAGAAGGCUCACCUGGAACAAAGGAUAGAGGAGCUGGAGUGUACAGUUCAUAAUCUUGAUGAUGAACGUAUGGAGCAAAUGUCAAAUAUGACUUUGAUGAAGGAAACCAUAAGCACUGUGGAAAAAGAAAUGAAAUCACUAGCAAGAAAGGCAAUGGAUACCGAAAGUGAACUUGGCAGACAAAAAGCAGAGAAUAAUUCUUUGAGACUUUUGUAUGAAAACACAGAAAAAGAUCUUUCUGAUACUCAGCGACACCUUGCUAAGAAAAAAUAUGAGCUACAGCUUACUCAGGAGAAAAUUAUGUGCUUGGAUGAAAAAAUUGAUAACUUUACAAGGCAAAAUAUUGCACAGCGAGAAGAAAUCAGCAUUCUUGGUGGAACCCUCAAUGAUCUGGCUAAAGAAAAGGAAUGCCUGCAAGCAUGUUUGGAUAAAAAAUCUGAGAAUAUUGCAUCCCUUGGAGAGAGUUUGGCAAUGAAAGAAAAGACCAUUUCAGGCAUGAAGAAUAUCAUUGCUGAGAUGGAACAGGCAUCAAGACAGUGUACUGAGGCCCUAAUUGUGUGUGAACAAGACGUUUCCAGAAUGCGUCGGCAAUUGGAUGAGACAAAUGAUGAGCUGGCCCAGAUCGCCAGGGAAAGAGAUAUCUUGGCUCAUGACAAUGACAAUCUCCAGGAACAGUUUGCUAAAGCUAAACAAGAAAACCAGGCACUGUCCAAAAAAUUGAAUGACACUCAUAAUGAACUUAAUGACAUAAAACAGAAGGUUCAAGAUACUAAUUUGGAGGUUAACAAGCUGAAGAAUAUAUUAAAGUCUGAAGAAUCUGAGAACCGGCAAAUGAUGGAACAACUUCGAAAAGCCAAUGAAGAUGCUGAAAACUGGGAAAAUAAAGCCCGUCAAUCAGAGGCAGAUAACAAUACCCUCAAACUGGAACUUAUCACUGCUGAGGCAGAGGGUAACAGAUUAAAAGAAAAAGUAGAUUCCCUCAACAGAGAGGUUGAGCAACACUUAAAUGCAGAAAGGUCUUACAAGUCCCAGAUUUCUACCUUACAUAAAUCUGUUGUAAAAAUGGAAGAGGAGCUUCAGAAGGUUCAGUUUGAAAAAGUGUCCGCUCUUGCAGAUUUGUCUUCUACUAGGGAACUCUGUAUUAAACUUGACUCAAGCAAAGAACUUCUUAAUCGACAGCUGGUUGCUAAAGAUCAAGAAAUAGAAAUGAGGGAGAAUGAGUUAGAUUCUGCUCAUUCUGAAAUUGAACUCCUGAGGAGUCAGAUGGCAAAUGAGAGAAUCUCCAUGCAGAAUCUAGAAGCUUUGCUGGUGGCCAAUCGAGACAAAGAAUAUCAGUCUCAGAUAGCACUUCAAGAAAAAGAAUCUGAAAUUCAGCUUCUUAAAGAACACCUUUGUUUGGCAGAAAAUAAAAUGGCCAUCCAGAGUAGAGAUGUGGCCCAGUUCAGAAAUGUUGUCACACAAUUGGAAGCUGAUUUAGACAUUACCAAAAGACAACUAGGAACAGAGCGCUUUGAAAGGGAGAGGGCCGUACAAGAACUUCGCCGCCAAAAUUAUUCAAGUAAUGCUUAUCAUAUGAGUUCUACAAUGAAGCCAAAUACAAAAUGUCAUUCACCAGAACGUGCUCACCAUCGAUCUCCUGACCGAGGCCUAGAUCGAUCAUUAGAAGAGAAUCUUUGCUACAGAGAUUUCUGACACCUGAAAUGAUUCUUCACAUCCCUGAGAAAGGUCAAAGUUACAAACUGAUUUUUUUUUUUUUGCUACAUGAGUGCAUUUAUCUUUUAAAUGCUUGGCAAUGUUAAAUGUAUUUAUUAACUUUGUGUCUCUGAAUCUCUGUUCUAAUGUGCCAUGUUGCAGUGAUCUGAGAUGACUUAUAAAAACAAAAAUGUAUAUGGCUCUUUCUAUCCAUGCAGUGAUAGUGAGUGUAAAAUCUGCUUACUUCACUAUUGAACACUAUUCUGUUCACUAUCUGGAGUAAAUAAAGAAGCUUAUUAAAACAGGGAAAAGUGUUUUUACAAAACUGCUUUCCUUUCCUUUCUUGGUAUCUCAAAUAAUUGGUUGGUUAAUUUUUUUUCUUUGUGAUUUGUGUUUUCAUGGCUGGAAAAUCUGUGCCAAAAUGGGUACAACUUACUGAUACUGGUCUGGGAUCUGAUAUUCCAUUUUGGAACCAACCUUACAUGAAUUCCAUGCCAUAAUCUGAUAUUGAAGCAGCAGAAAGUAGGAGUGUUGUCAGGGUUUUAAAACCUAUAGUAUUGUACCACUCAAAGACUAAGUAACAUACAUAUUCUACAAUUGUGUUUACUACUACUGCUUUUAGAAAGGUAGGUGAUGGUAUAUCUGUCAAGAAUGUAAGAUUUUAUUAAAAAUCUUUAUUUUUAAUAAGUUUUCUUUCAAGUACUGCAAUCAACUUAAUUGCGAUUUUAUUUUAUUGUCUGUGGCAGCUGUCUGUAAUCUGGAGUAAUAAGAUAAGUGAUGUUUCCUUCCUCCCCCAAUUUCCUAAAUCUCUUACCUUAUCUAUCCAUAGGCUUUGAUGUAAUGUUCAUAUUAGAGCCUGAAUGCUACUGUAUUUUACUGAUAUAAACUAUUUGUAUUCUUGCCAUUUUAAUAAAAAAAGGCUUGUCAUUAAUAGUA